AAGGUCCUGGGCAUCUCCGUCCCGGGAAGGCUUAAGCAGGUAAAGCAGUCACUGUGAAGAAAAUAACAUUUUAAGAAACUUUUCUGUCACAAUUGAUAGAGGAAAAGCCAGUAGAGAAGUACAUCUUCUUGUGUGUGUGUCUCAUCGUGCCACUUUUUGUAACUCAGCUUAGUAAUGAAGCCACCAUUAUGUCCUCAGUCAGUGAAGUAAAUGUGGAUAUAAAAGAUUUCCUAAUGAGCAUUAAUUUGGAGCAGUAUCUCUUACAUUUCCAUGAGUCUGGUUUUACUACUGUGAAGGACUGUGCAGCAAUAAAUGACAGCCUGCUGCAGAAAAUUGGAAUAUCACCUACAGGUCACCGUAGGAGGAUACUUAAACAGUUACAGAUAAUCUUGUCAAAAAUGCAAGAUAUUCCAAUAUAUGCAAAUGUUCAUAAAACUAAGAAGAAUGAUGACCCUUCAAAGGAUUACCAUGUUCCAUCUUCUGAUCAGAAUAUCUGCAUAGAACUUUCCAAUUCUGGUAGUGUUCAGACAUCUAGCCCACCGCAGUUGGAGACUGUUAGAAAAAAUCUUGAAGACAGUGAUGCAAGUGUGGAAAGAAGCCAGUAUCCUCAAUCAGAUGAUAAGCUGUCUCCUCCUAAACGCGACUUCCCCACUGCAGAGGAACCACACCUGAAUUUGGGUUCUUUGAAUGAUUCUUUAUUUGGUAGUGACAAUAUUAAAAUAGAAUCAUUGAUUACAAAGAAGACUGUGGAUCACACAGUUGAAGAACAACAAACAGAAAAAGUUAAAUUGAUCACAGAAAAUCUCAGUAAGCUCCCUAAUGCAGACUCUGAAUGCCUUUCUUUUGUUGGCUGUUCAACAUCAGGAACAAAUUCUGGAAAUGGAACAAAUGGUUUAUUAGAAGGAUCACCACCAUCCCCAUUCUUUAAGUUUCAAGGAGAAAUGAUUGUAAAUGACUUGUAUGUUCCAUCAUCACCAAUCCUAGCACCUGUGAGAAGUCGUAGCAAGUUGGUUUCAAGACCAUCUCGAUCUUUUCUGCUAAGACAUCGACCUGUACCAGAGAUUCCAGGGUCAACAAAAGGAGUUUCUGGGAGCUAUUUCCGUGAAAGAAGAAAUGUUGCUACCUCAACUGAAAAAUCUGUGGCAUGGCAAAAUUCAAAUGAGGAGAAUUCAUCUUCCAUCUUUCCUUAUGGAGAGACCUUUCUCUUCCAGAGACUAGAAAAUUCCAAGAAGCGAUCUAUAAAGAAUGAAUUUUUGACCCAGGGAGAAGCACUCAAAGGGGAAGCAGCUACUGCAACAAACUCUUUUAUCAUCAAAUCAAGCAUAUACGAUAACAGAAAGGAGAAAAUAAGCGAGGACAAGGUGGAAGAUAUUUGGAUACCUCGAGAGGACAAAAACAAUUUUUUGAUAGACACUGCUUCUGAAUCAGAAUACUCAACAGUAGAAGAAUGCUUUCAGAGUUUAAGAAGAAAAAAUUCAAAGGCAUCUAAAUCUAGGACUCAAAAAGCCUUGAUUUUGGACUCCGUUAAUAGGCACAGUUAUCCGUUAAGCUCAACAAGUGGAAAUGCUGAUUCAUCAGCCGUUUCUUCACAGGCAAUAUCUCCCUAUGCCUGCUUUUAUGGAGCAUCUGCAAAGAAGGUUAAAUCAGGAUGGCUGGAUAAACUCUCUCCUCAAGGAAAACGCAUGUUUCAAAAGAGAUGGGUGAAAUUUGAUGGCCUUAGCAUUUCUUACUACAAUAAUGAGAAGGAGAUGUAUUCGAAAGGAAUAAUUCCCCUUUCUGCUAUAUCAACAGUACGAGUUCAAGGAGACAACAAAUUUGAAGUUGUUACAACACAAAGAACUUUUGUUUUUAGAGUAGAAAAAGAAGAGGAGAGAAAUGACUGGAUCAGCAUACUAUUAAAUGCACUGAAAUCACAAUCCCUUACCUCGCAGUCUCAAGCUGUUGUUACACCUGAGAAAUGUGGAUAUCUUGAAUUGAGAGGCUAUAAGGCAAAAAUUUUUACUGUGUUAAGUGGAAACAGUGUGUGGCUUUGCAAAAACGAACAGGAUUUUAAGAGUGGACUUGGUAUUACCAUAAUUCCUAUGAAUGUAGCAAAUGUAAAGCAAGUGGACCGAACUGUGAAACAAUCUUUUGAAAUAAUCACUCCCUACAGGAGUUUCAGCUUUACAGCCGAGACUGAAAAGGAGAAACAAGACUGGAUUGAAGCUGUGCAGCAAUCAAUAGCAGAAACUCUCUCUGAUUAUGAAGUAGCUGAGAAGAUUUGGUUCAAUGAAUCCAACAGGAGCUGUGCAGAUUGUAAAGCCCCAGAUCCUGACUGGGCAUCCAUCAAUCUCUGUGUUGUCAUCUGUAAGAAGUGUGCAGGACAGCAUAGAUCUUUAGGACCAAAAGAUUCCAAGGUUAGAAGUCUAAAAAUGGAUGCUAGCAUUUGGAGCAAUGAACUCAUCGAGCUUUUUAUUGUCAUUGGAAACAAAAGAGCAAAUGACUUUUGGGCUGGUAAUCUUCAAAAGGAUGAAGAAUUACAUAUGGACUCACCAGUAGAAAAGAGAAAAAACUUUAUUACUCAGAAAUAUAAAGAAGGAAAAUUCAGAAAAACUCUUUUGGCAUCUCUCACCAAAGAAGAAUUAAAUAAGGCUCUAUGUGCUGCUGUAGUGAAACCGGAUGUUCUAGAAACAAUGGCUUUGCUGUUCAGUGGAGCAGAUGUCAUGUGUGCCACCGGAGACCCCGUGCAUAGCACCCCCUAUCUGCUAGCCAAGAAAGCUGGGCAAAGUCUGCAAAUGGAAUUUCUCUACCAUAACAAAUUCUCAGAUUUCCCUCAACAUGAUAUUCAUUCCGAGGGUGUAUUAAGUCAAGAGUCUUCCCAGUCCACAUUCCUCUGUGACUUUUUAUAUCAAGCUCCUUCUGCUGCUUCUAAACUCUCUUCAGAGAAAAAACUGCUUGAAGAGACAAAUAAAAAAUGGUGUGUUUUGGAAGGAGGCUUCUUGAGUUACUAUGAAAAUGAUAAGUCUACCACACCUAAUGGCACCAUUAAUAUCAAUGAAGUUAUCUGCCUGGCUAUACACAAAGAGGACUUCUAUUUAAAUACUGGGCCCAUCUUUAUCUUUGAGAUCUACUUACCCUCCGAACGUGUGUUUUUAUUUGGAGCUGAAACAUCUCAAGCUCAAAGAAAAUGGACAGAGGCAAUAGCCAAGCAUUUUGUUCCCUUAUUUGCUGAAAACUUAACAGAAGCUGACUAUGAUUUGAUUGGUCAACUCUUCUACAAAGACUGCCAUGCCCUGGAUCAGUGGAGAAAAGGCUGGUUUGCUAUGGACAAAUCCAGCUUGCAUUUUUGCCUUCAAAUGCAAGAAGUUCAGGGAGAUAGAAUGCACUUAAGAAGACUGCAAGAGCUAACAAUCAGCACAAUGGUUCAAAAUGGGGAAAAACUGGAUGUUUUACUCUUGGUAGAAAAAGGGAGAACAUUAUACAUCCAUGGGCAUACCAAGUUGGAUUUCACAGUCUGGCAUACUGCAAUUGAAAAAGCAGCAGGUACAGAUGGUAAUGCUUUACAAGAUCAGCAGCUCAGCAAAAAUGACGUUCCCAUUAUAGUGAACAGCUGUAUAGCAUUUGUUACACAGUAUGGUUUAGGAUGCAAAUAUAUCUAUCAAAAGAAUGGUGAUCCUUUGCAUAUAAGUGAACUCCUGGAGAGUUUCAAAAAGGAUGCAAGAAGCUUUAAAUUGAGGGCUGGAAAACAUCAGCUUGAAGAUGUGACGGCUGUGUUGAAAAGUUUUCUCUCUGACAUUGAUGAUGCACUGCUUACUAAGGAGCUCUACCCAUAUUGGAUCUCUGCUUUAGAUACGCAAGAUGACAAGGAAAGAAUUAAAAAAUAUGGAGCAUUUAUACGUUCUCUUCCAGGGGUCAACCGAGCAACACUAGCAGCUAUCAUUGAACACCUGUAUAGGGUUCAGAAAUGCUCAGAAAUCAAUCACAUGAAUGCCCAUAAUUUGGCCUUGGUCUUUUCAUCCUGUUUGUUUCAAACGAAGGGACAAACUAGUGAAGAAGUGAAUGUAAUUGAGGACCUAAUUAAUAAUUAUGUAGAAAUAUUUGAGGUUUCCCAGGCUGGAGAUUUGUUAAUUGAAGUAUAUGUAGAAAGGAAGGAACCCGACUGUAGUAUUAUAAUUCGGAUAUCUCCUGUGAUGGAAGCAGAAGAAUUAACUAAUGAUAUAUUAGCGAUAAAAAAUAUUAUUCCUACAAAAGGUGAUAUUUGGGCCACAUUUGAAGUCAUUGAAAAUGAAGAGCUAGAGCGUCCUCUUCACUACAAGGAAAAUGUACUGGAGCAGGUGCUUCGGUGGAGUUCAUUAGCUGAACCUGGCUCUGCUUACCUGGUGGUGAAGAGAUUCUUAACCGCUGACACAAUUAAACACUGCAGUGACCGGAGUACACUGGGAAGCAUCAAAGAAGGAAUCUUGAAAAUCAAAGAAGAACCAUCCAAAAUACUAUCUGGAAAUAAGUUUCAAGACCGGUAUUUUGUUUUACGAGAUGGGUUUCUCUUUCUUUACAAGGAUGUGAAGAGUAGUAAACAUGACAAGAUGUUUUCUCUCAGUUCCAUGAAGUUUUAUCGUGGAGUGAAAAAGAAAAUGAAGCCUCCAACAAGCUGGGGAUUGACCGCAUAUUCUGAGAAACAUCACUGGCACCUGUGUUGUGAUAGUUCACGAACUCAGACGGAGUGGAUGACCAGUAUCUUUAUUGCCCAGCAUGAAUAUGAUAUAUGGCCACCAGCUGGAAAGGAACGAAAACGUUCAAUAACCAAAAAUCCCAAAAUUGGAGGUUUGCCUCUGAUUCCUAUACAGCAUGAGGGGAAUGCAACCUUGGCCCGGAAAAAUAUUGAGAGAGACCCUUGUGAGCAUACAAGCUCUCAUUUGGAAGCCUCGGGAAGCCAUAUGGUUGGAGCAGGUAUGAAUUGGAAUCUUGACAGAACAUCAUCAAAACUGCCCACAACCUCAAUUCAGCUCAGUCCCAUUGGAUCAGGAUCAUCAGCCUCCUCUUUGCCAGAAGAUGGAAAGGUAAAUCCUCUAUGGAACUUCUCUAUUUUUUUUUUUUUCAAUUUCUGGCAUUUAAAAAUGAAGAAAAAGGAAAAAAAUUCAAGACAAUUGACCCUUUGACCAAAAUGCUAAGAUGAAAAUAUAGACAAUAGAAAGAAAUCCCCAAAUGAUCAAGCUGUUAGAAUUACCAAAGAAGGACUAAAUAACAGCAAUGAUUGAUAUUAAUAUUAACAAGAAAAUAGACAAAAAAUACAGAAAAUAUUGGAUAAUUCUGUCAGAGAAUUGGAAUUUUAAAAAAUCAAAUAAAAAUUUUAGAAGUUAAAAACAUAGUAACUAAAGUUAAAAACAAAUGGGUUUUAUAGCAUAAUUGACAUGCACCAACGGUUAGUGAAUUGGAGACAGGUUAGUAAAAAAAAUCAAAUAUAUCCAAAAUGAACACACAGAAAAAAAUAUGUAGAUAAAAGAAGUAUGUGAGACACUGUUAAAAUGUCAAACAUAUAUAUAAUGUGUUAUCUAGAAAAUUGGGAGGAGGCAAUAUUGGAGGAGAAAAUGACCAACAGUUUUUUUAAAUGGAUAUGUUAUUUAUACCAAUAGAUUCAAUAUGUUAGCCGAACUCUAAGCAAGGUAAAUUAAAAAAAAAAACCUACACAAAAUUACAUUGUAAUAAAACAAUGGAAAAGUCACUGAGGGACUCUUAAAAUCAUCCAGAGAAUACCGAAACCCCAAACUUAGAGUAAUAACAAUACAAUGACAGUGGCCUCUCACCAUAAAAGAGGAAAGCCAAAAAAAAAACAAUUACAAUUAUUAAAGUGCUAUAUGAAAAUAUAUGCCAACUAGAAUUCCAUAUCCCUUAAAAUAUUCCUUGAAAGAGAUGGCAAAAUAAAGGCUACUUUGGAAAAAGAGAUUUCCUCAGUCAAGCUGCACUGAAAAAAAAAAACAACAAAAAACUACAGAUAAUGUUUUAGAUAGAGAGAAAUUGGUCCUAUGUAGAAGUGCCAAAAUGCAGUAAAACUAAAGAGCAAAGGAAAGUAAAAAAAAAAAAUCAGGUAAACAUAAUAUUGACUGUACUAAAUGAUGAUAUAAUGUCUUGUGAAUAAAUGUGCAAGCAUUGUCAGGGAAGAAGUGAAUGUAAUUAUUUGUAUUAGUUACAAUGUCAAGGAUGUGUGCUUUAAUUUCUGAGGUACCUGCUAAAAGAAAAGUGAAAGAACAUAUGACUUUCAUGCUUAUAGAAAAGAAAAAUGGAAAACUAAAAUAUAUUUUAGUAAUUCAAAGUAGAAAAAAAGAAAAAGGGACAAAAACAGGUCACACUGAAAACAAUAGUAGUAAGGUGGUAGAUAUAAGGCUAAAUAUAUCAGUAAUUACAUACAAAACUAAGCACUUCAAUUAAAAGCAAACGACAAGAAAACCUAUACAUGUUCUGGUUCUCAGAGACACACAUAAAAUAUAUAGACAUAUGUUGAAAGUAAAAGUUUGAAAAAGAUAUAUACUCUGCAGAUAGUAAUCUAAAGAAAACUGAUUUCCCAAAACUAACAAAAUACAAAGUUGUCUUUAAGGCAGGAAACAUUACUUCAGGUAGAGACAUUGCUUGUAAAGGAGUGGUCAUUUCACCAGGGAGUUAAAUAAAUAAACUCUUUACAGUUCCAACAAAAUGGUAAGCUUCAAGGGUCACAGUCCAGGUUUCACGUUCAUGCUGUAAGAAGAUGAACUCCAGACAAGGGAAGUGCCUACUAUGGUACAAAUUGAACUCUAUAAAUUUGCUCUGGCCCUAGUGCAAGUGUAUAUACCCCACAUACUUUAUACAAAUGGUUACAUUGAUAAAAGAAUUUGUAUUAUUAUAGUUUUAUAUUGAAAAUAGUUCAGGACCUAUUGAAAGUAGCCAAUAUACUUGAGUACAUUUGUAUUAAUCCCAUGUUUCUUAAUCAUUUUCUGCCCAGCUACUCAAGUACCUAAUAAAAAUAGAGUAACAUUUAAUGAAAUAUAUUUCUUCUUUGUUAGAUGAACUUAGCUUUUGCUCCCAAGGAAUUUAUCUGGUUUGUGCUAUCAUGUAUGUAUUAUUAUUACUAAAUACCAACUCUUGCCCACUCUGAAAUAAAAGUGUGAAAUUACCUUAUAAACGUACCUGAAACUGGCUGGGCGCAGUGGCUCACGCCUGUAAUCCCAGCACUUUGGGAGGCCAAGGCUGGUUGGUCACCUGAGGUCAGGAGUUCAAGACCAUCCUGGCCAACAUGGUGAAACCCCGUCUCUACUAAAAAUACAAAAAUUAGCUUGUCAUGGUGGUACAUGCCUGUAAUCCCAGCUCCUUGGGAGGUUGAGGUAGGAGAAUCAGUUGAACCCAGGAGGCAGAGGUUGUGGUGAGCCAAGAUCACGCCAUUGCACUCCAGCCUGGGCGACAGAGUGAGACUCCAUCUCAAAAAAAUAAAUAAAUAAAAAUAAAAAUAAAAAUAAGUACCUGAAACUAAAUGGUUAAAUCAGUCACUUCCCACACUAUGAGACUGCUGAGUUGAAUCAGGAAAUUAGACAUAUAACAACUAUUUUAGAACAAGUUAGAAAUCAAACAUUUGACAUGCUAAAUCAAAUUACCAGAGAUGCGAUGGUUCUUAUGAGGAUGAUUUUCCAAAACACAAUGACUUUCUGUUUUACUCCAUCUCAUGAAUAAAUAAACAGUGUGCAUUCACGGGCAAAGAACAAUAUGGACACAUUCCAAAUAAAGCAGAUCUUAUCCAAGAUUUUAUAACCAUAUUACAAAAUUACAGGAUUGAGGUUUCCUAUCAGGGCCUUAGUGGAAACGCUAAAUCUCAUUCAGUGACAGAUGUUGUACCUAUGUCUCGGGAUUCAAAAACUUAAAAUAUUUUAAAUGCACUCAUAGAUCCAAUAUAAUCAAAAUACUAGAGCUGUUUAAAUCAUUUAUAUCAGUUGACUGUACAAAUGACAAAACCCUUAGGGUUAUUACGUAUUUUAAAAGACAUAACCUGCAAUCACUUAAAGUCAUUAAACUUAAAUAGUGAAUUCCUAGCAAUACACAUUUUAAAUUACUACUGCAAAAGAAAUAAACUCCUGACCUCAUUUGUAAUCCAUCACCAAUCAUUAUAAAAUGUCCUUAAAGUAGACUACAGACUAUCAGGGGAUCUUCUAUUAUGCCCUAGGACAAAGUACUUAAAAAGUAUUUCUCUGAUGACUGUGUAAUAUGAGUAGUCAUCAGCUUUACACUUAGUGAAAAGUAUUUCCAGAUUGUGAUAAAAGCUUAUUUGGUAGUAUGUGGUAAUGAUGUAAUAUUUUUUGUUUAAUGUUAUUUUGUGUAUUCAUUUGUUUAUUUUGCCUUUUAUGUUUGCUUUUUCCAUUUUGUGCAUGGUAAUUAAAUAAAAAAAUUGGAAAGUCUCA